GAGCUCCCGGAACCGCCGCCUCUAGGGAUGGACGGUCAGACUCUGCGAAAGGCCGAGAGAAGCUGGUCCUGCUCACGAGAGAAAAAGGAGGGUUACGCUAAGGACAUGGUGACAGACUUUGAUGAGAAACAUGAUGAGUAUUUAAUAUUGCUUCAGCAGAGGAACCGGAUAUUAAAGCAUUUGAAAAGCAAGGACCCCGUGCAAUUGAGGCUGGAGCACUUGGAGCAAGGUUUCUCUGUCUAUGUCAACGGUGCCAAUUCGGAGCUGAAAUCAUCACCGCGGAAAGCUAUUCACUCUGACUUCUCCAGAAGUGCCUCCCACACGGAGGGGACACACGAUUAUGGACGAAGAACUCUGUUUCGAGAAGCUGAAGAAGCCUUAAGACGCAGUUCACGGACAGCCCCCAGUAAAGUCCAGCGCCGAGGAUGGCACCAGAAAUCUGUGCAGAUCAGAACAGAAGCUGGCCCACGGCUCCACAUCGAACCUCCUGUGGACUAUUCUGAUGAUUUUGAGCUGUGUGGGGAUGUGACUCUCCAGGCAAACAACACUUCUGAGGAUCGUCCGCAGGAUACCAAAUCUCCCACCAGUACCAAGCCCUGUGGUUUUAACUUCUCCCUUCUGAAUGCAUGUGGACAUUCUGACCCUUCAAGCAGCGUGGACAAAGAAAGGAUCCUCUUAACUAUUCAGGAUGUGAUGGAGCUGAGAAGAAGCCUGGAACUUAGUGUAAAUCUACAAAGGAAACAAAAGGAUUGUUCCAGCGAUGAGUAUGACUCUAUUGAGGAAGACAUACUCUCUGAGCCUGAGCCAGAGGACCCGGCACUGGUGGGCCAUCCCAGACAUGACCGCCCUCCUUCCAGUGGCGACUGGACUCAGAAAGAUGUUCACGGGGAACAGGAGACAGAAGGACGCUCUUCUCCAGGCCCAGACACCCUCGUGGUGCUGGAAUUUAACCCAGCUUCCAAAAGUCAUAAAAGGGAAAGGAAUUUGUCUGCAAAGCGGAAGGACAAUGCUGAGGUUUUCGUUCCCACCAAACCUGAGCCAAACCUGACUCCCCAAGCUCCUGCUGUAUUCCCAGACCAGGAGAGGAUGUGCUCCAGACCUGGAAGCCGGCGAGAGAGACCCCUGUCUGCAACCCGCAAAACUCUUUGCGAGGCUGAGUACCCAGAGGAAGAUGCCUCUGCUGUGCUCCAAGCCAUCCAGGUGGAGAACGCAGCCCUGCAGAGGGCGCUCCUCAGCAGAAAGGCCGAGCAGCCAGCCAGCCCACUGCAGCAUGGAGUGAAUGGCUUUGUUCCAACAUCACAUCAUGUGAUCACAUCCUUCCAGGAUGCAGAAGGACCACCAGCAAAACCAUGGACCAGUCUGCUGGAGGAGAAGGAAGAGACCCUUGAGCUGCUUCCCAUCACCACGGCGACUACUACUCAGGAGCCGGCCGGGGCAGCAGGAGGAGCCAGGGCCAUCAACCAGGCCAUGGACAGAAUUGGGCUUCUGGGAAGCAGACAACAGCAGAAGCUUCUGAAAGUCCUCCAGGCCGUCGAAAGUGACUCUGCCCAUCUCGGCAGGGUGGUUUCACCAACCAAGGAGCAAGUAUCAGACACAGAGGACAAACAGAGAAUGAGGGCAGACGAGAUCAAAGAUGCCAUCUACGUGACCAUGGAGAUCCUGUCCAACUGGGGCAACUCGUGGUGGGUGGGUCUCACAGAAGUCGAGUUCUUUGACUUGAAUGACACAAAGCUUUAUGUGUCGCCCCACGAUGUGGAUAUCCGGAACACAGCCACGCCUGGGGAGCUGGGCCGCCUCGUCAACAGGAACUUAGCUGGCAAGAAAGACUCCUCCCCGUGGACCUGCCCCUUCCACCCACCACUCCAGCUGUUUUUUGUUAUUCGAAACACAAGACAGCUGGGGGACUUCCAUCUGGCCAAGAUCAAGGUUCGGAAUUACUGGACAGCUGAUGGCGAUCUUGACAUUGGUGCCAAGAACGUGAAGCUUUACGUCAACAGAAACCUCAUCUUCAAUGGCAAGUUAGACAAAGGAGAUAGGGAGGCCCCAGCUGACCACAGCAUCCUGGUUGACCAGAAGAACGAGAAGAGCGAGCAACUAGAGGAGGCCAUGAACGCUCACUCGGAAGAAAGCAAAGGCACCCAUGAGAUGGCUGGUGCCAGCGGGGACAAGGAGCUUGGUCUCGGUUGCUCACCGCCAGCUGAAACAUUAGCGGAUGCAAAGCUUUCUUCACAAGGAAAUGUGUCUGGCAAAAGAAAGAAUUCUACUAAUUGCAGGAAAGACAGUUUGUCCCAGUUAGAGGAAUAUUUGAGACUGUCGGCAGUCCCCACUUCGAUGGGUGACAUGCCCAGUGCUCCUGCCACUUCCCCACCUGUGAAGUGCCCUCCUGUCCAUGAGGAGCCCUCUCUCAUCCAACAACUGGAAAACCUCAUGGGCAGAAAAAUCUGUGAGCCACCCGGGAAAACCCCAUCCUGGUUACAACCUUCUCCCACCGGCAAGGACAGGAAGCAGGGAGGCAGGAAGCCAAAACCCCUCUGGCUUAGUCCCGAGAAGCCCCUGGCCUGGAAGGGCAGGCUCCCAUCAGACGAUGUCAUCGGUGAGGGUCCUGGAGAGACCGAGGCCAGGGAUAAAGGCCUACGGCAUGAGCCAGGGUGGGGGACCAGCCGGAGUGUCAACACCAAGGAGAGACCCCAGAGGGCAACCACCAAAGUCCACAGUGAUGACUCAGACAUCUUUAACCAGCCCCCCAACAGAGAGCGCCCUGCUAGUGGGAGGAGGGGCUCAAGGAAGGAUGCUGGCAGCAGUAGUCAUGGGGACGACCAGCCAGCCAGCAGAGAAGACACCUGGUCUUCCAGGACGCCGUCACGGUCAAGGUGGCGCAGUGAGCAGGAGCACACACUUCACGAGUCAUGGAGCUCCCUCAGUGCCUUCGACCGCUCCCACCGGGGACGCAUCUCCAACACGGAGCUCCCGGGGGACAUCCUGGAUGAGCUCCUGCAGCAAAAGAGCAGCCGGCACAGCGACUUGCCCCCCUCCAAGAAGGGGGAGCAGCCAGGGCUGUCGAGAGGGCAGGAUGGCUACUCUGGAGAGACAGACGCUGGGGGUGACUUUAAAAUCCCCGUCUUGCCUUAUGGACAGCGCUUGGUCAUUGACAUCAAGUCUACCUGGGGGGACAGACACUAUGUCGGCCUCAACGGAAUAGAAAUAUUCAGUUCCAAGGGUGAACCGGUGCAGAUUUCAAACAUAAAAGCAGACCCUCCCGAUAUCAAUAUUUUACCAGCCUAUGGGAAAGACCCCCGCGUGGUCACCAACCUCAUCGACGGGGUGAACAGGACCCAGGAUGACAUGCAUGUCUGGCUGGCCCCCUUCACGCGGGGCAGAUCCCACUCCAUCACCAUUGACUUCACGCACCCUUGCCACGUUGCCCUGAUCAGAAUUUGGAACUACAAUAAAUCUCGGAUACAUUCCUUCCGAGGCGUGAAGGACAUCACAAUGCUGUUAGACACCCAGUGCAUCUUUGAAGGAGAAAUCGCCAAGGCCUCUGGAACCCUGGCGGGAGCCCCAGAGCACUUUGGAGACACGAUCUUAUUCACAACCGAUGAUGACAUUCUCGAGGCCAUAUUCUAUUCUGAUGAGAUGUUUGACCUGGAUGUGGGGAGCCUGGACAGCCUGCAGGAUGAAGAGGCAAUGAGGAGGCCCAGCACGGCCGACGGCGAGGGGGAUGAGCGGCCCUUCACCCAGGCUGGCUUGGGGGCUGAUGAACGGAUCCCGGAGCUAGAGCUCCCAUCCAGUUCCCCUGUCCCCCAAGUCACCACGCCAGAGCCAGGCAUCUACCACGGAAUCUGCCUUCAGCUGAAUUUCACUGCCUCCUGGGGAGACUUGCACUACCUGGGGCUCACUGGCCUGGAAGUGGUGGGCAAGGAGGGCCAGGCGCUGCCCAUCCACCUGCACCAGAUCUCUGCUUCCCCCAGAGACUUAAAUGAGCUCCCCGAGUACUCUGACGACUCCCGGGCCCUGGACAAGUUAAUUGAUGGCACCAACAUCACCAUGGAGGAUGAGCAUAUGUGGCUGAUCCCCUUCUCGCCGGGGCUGGACCAUGUGGUCACGAUCCGCCUGGACAGGGCCGAAAGCAUCGCAGGCCUGCGCUUCUGGAACUACAAUAAAUCUCCCGAGGACACCUAUCGCGGGGCCAAGAUUGUCCACGUCUCCCUGGAUGGCCUGUGCGUCUCCCCGCCAGAGGGCUUUCUCAUCCGGAAGGGGCCAGGCAACUGCCACUUUGAUUUUGCUCAAGAAAUCCUCUUCGUGGACUACCUACGGGCUCAGCUGCUGCCCCAGCCGGCCAGGAGGCUGGACAUGAGAAGCCUGGAGUGUGCAAGCAUGGACUACGAGGCACCGCUGAUGCCCUGUGGCUUCAUUUUCCAGUUUCAGCUUCUCACCAGCUGGGGCGACCCCUACUACAUCGGCCUCACCGGCCUGGAGCUGUAUGACGAGCGAGGAGAAAAAAUCCCCUUGUCGGAAAACAAUAUUGCGGCCUUCCCCGACAGCGUGAACUCCCUGGAGGGUGUGGGCGGGGACGUCCGCACCCCAGACAAGCUCAUCGACCAAGUGAACGACACCAGUGAUGGCCGGCACAUGUGGCUGGCUCCCAUCCUGCCGGGCCUGGUGAACCGGGUUUAUGUGAUUUUCGAUCUGCCUACCACCGUGUCAAUGAUCAAACUGUGGAAUUAUGCGAAAACACCCCAUCGAGGGGUGAAGGAGUUUGGCCUCCUGGUGGACGACCUGCUUGUGUACAAUGGGAUCCUGGCCAUGGUGAGCCACCUGGUGGGGGGCAUCCUGCCCACAUGUGAGCCCACCGUGCCCUACCACACCAUCCUCUUCACCGAGGACAGGGACAUCCGCCACCAGGAGAAACACACCACCAUCAGUAAUCAGGCCGAGGAUCAAGAUGUCCAGAUGAUGAAUGAAAACCAAAUCAUUACCAACGCGAAACGGAAGCAGAGCGUUGUUGACCCAGCCUUACGUCCCAAAACCUGCAUCAGCGAGAAGGAGACGAGACGACGGCGCUGCUGACUGGUGAAGGAGGGAGAGCUGGUCCUCCCACUAUGGUGGGCUCCGUCAGCAGCCCCACUCAGUGCCUGCGUCCCUCACCCUCAGUCCCAGGAGCUGGAAGCGAACCACAGUGUUGAGGGGAGCCCGCUGGGAAGAGGGGACUCGGGAGGACAGCCCUGGAUACUACCAGAGUGACAGAUGGCUGUGGCUGCAGGGCAAAGAGAUCCCCUGCAGUUCUGGGUUGGCCACAGGGAGCCCAGGACACCCGCCUUCAUGCCUCUGCUGUGAGACCCAGCAAAGCAGGGCCCAUGACCACUAGGGCCUGGGCUGACCCUGACUCAGAACAGGACAAUGACGGGGUGGGGAGGCAUCCCAUCCAGCCUCAGAGGGCCCAGAGAAUGGCUGAGCAGGACAGUGGGAGACCAGACCCUACCCCGCAACUCCAGUAAGCAGGGCACUGCCCAGGGAGACUGCCUUCAGAAACCUGAGCUUCAGCGGCCAACACCCCCCAUCCCCUGCGCAUCCUUGUCUCAUUUGGGGACUGGUGGAGCUGGCUGAGAGGUUGGGGUAGUUUCCUGGUUACAGGGGUCCACAAGACCCUCUCUCAUCCCGGUAUAGGGGCCUCUCUCCUCUCAUCGGGCCUGAUAAGGGAUUGGCCAAGGCUGUGUGCAUCCUGCAGAGGGAAGGAAGUCAGCUGGGCCACCCGCCAUCCACCUUGGCAAGAGCUGGGCCCACUCUGGCAGGCCAGGGUAUCAUCUGCGUGCUGCUGCCGGGCCAGGAAGGGUGGGUGGGUGGCCAGCAGGCUGGCAGCUCCAGACCCCAGAGGGCCAGAAGAACUCACCCCAGUGCCCUCUGGAUGCAGGUGUUGGGGAACACUGAGGACAAUCCCCCAUCUCCCCUCACCCUUGAGCAGGCCCUCCCUGCACUCUCUGCCACAUGUCCCUCCUGGUCUGAUCACGGCUGUGCUCACUGAUGUGGCUGCUUUCUGUCUCUGCCCCUGUGCCCUUGGAGGCAGGCAGUGAGGUGCUCCUUUCCCAGGCCCCCACCCCUUCUCCCCCUUCAGCCACUUCCCAGCGAGUUGGAAAUGUGCCUUGCACCCCCAGCCGAGUGAAGCCCAGAACGCAUCUAUAUGCAUCGAUGUAACAAGCUCGGAUCAGGGACCUAAUUGGUUUCCCAGUAGUGGGUAAUUUCUCGUUGCAAAUAUUAAUCCGUUGUUUUUCUGGCGCCCAGCCCGGCCCGCCGCAGUACUGUACUCGAGGUACGUUCCUAUGCAACCGAGAGCCCCGGCAAAUACUUCAUGAGCUUAGCAGCCUGGGCUCGAGCAGCUAUGCAAACGCGCUUUUCAUUUGGAGCACGGGGCUGAUGUGAAGAUAAGAAUUGUUUCUCCUGGAGAAAGAUCCAUCAUUUCUCCAGCUUCCAAGCCCCCGGCACCUCUGCUCAGCUCCCAGAUGUGACGAGCACCUCCCGCCAGGGGGAGUCAGGGGUUGAUCAAACCAGCUCUUGUGACCCAAACCAGUGCCGCUGCAUUAAAGGGAGGCCCAGCUACUCCUUCCCAGCUGAGAUGUGGGUACAGGUCAGAUUUGUCAGGGAGAUGGCACUAACACGACACAAGCUCACUCCCAGAACCGCAGCUGAUGUUUAUAAUAAUCGUAUGUACUGUGCAAUUUAGGAGGGGAAAAAAAGGCUGUACAAGCUUUAACUCUAAAAUAAAUUUCUAUUUUUUUCCUCUUGCAAAA